CCAGGAAGUCCGCCACAGCCCUCCCCAGCGCAGCGCGAGCGCGGGCCAGAGCGCAGCGGCCGCGGGCACUCCAGGGAGGCCCGGGGGCGGGCAGCCCGGCGGCCGCCUAGCUGCCCCCAGCCAGGGCCCCGGGAGGGAGGGGCUCGGACGGGCCUUAGAAACUCACCAAGAACUAACACGCGCAGCCCGGCAGUCCCGCUGCCCACUGCGGCGGCGAGCAUGGACGCGGUGUUGCUGGAGCACUUCCCCGGGGGCCUAGACGCCUUUCCUUCUUCGUACUUCGACGAGGACGACUUCUUCACCGACCAGUCUUCACGGGACCCCCUGGAGGACGGCGAUGAGCUGCUGGCGGACGAGCAGGCCGAGGUGGAGUUCCUUAGCCACCAGCUCCACGAGUACUGCUACCGCGACGGGGCGUGCCUGCUGCUGCAGCCCGCGCCCCCGGCCGCCCCGCUAGCGCUCGCCCCGCCGUCCUCGGGGGGCCUCGGUGAGCCAGACGACGGCGGCGGCGGCGGCUACUGCUGCGAGACGGGGGCGCCCCCAGGCGGCUUCCCCUACUCGCCCGGCUCGCCGCCCUCGUGCCUGGCCUACCCGUGCGCCGGGGCGGCAGUACUGUCUCCCGGGGCGCGGCUGCGCGGCCUGAGCGGAGCGGCGGCUGCGGCGGCGCGGCGCCGGCGGCGGGUGCGCUCCGAGGCGGAGCUGCAGCAGCUGCGGCAGGCGGCCAACGUGCGCGAGCGGCGGCGCAUGCAGUCCAUCAACGACGCCUUCGAGGGGCUGCGCUCGCACAUCCCCACGCUGCCCUACGAGAAGCGCCUCUCCAAGGUGGACACGCUGCGCCUGGCCAUCGGCUACAUCAACUUCCUCAGCGAGCUCGUGCAGGCCGACCUGCCCUUGCGCGGCGGUGGCGCGGGCGGCUGCGGGGGGCCGGGCGGCGGCGGGCGCCUGGGCGGGGACAGCCCGGGCAGCCAGGCCCAGAAGGUCAUCAUCUGCCAUCGGGGCACCCGGUCCCCCUCCCCCAGCGACCCUGAUUAUGGCCUCCCUCCCCUAGCAGGACACUCUCUCUCAUGGACUGAUGAAAAACAACUCAAGGAACAAAAUAUUAUCCGAACAGCCAAAGUCUGGACCCCAGAGGACCCCAGAAAACUCAACAGCAAAUCUUCCUUCAACAACAUAGAAAACGAACCACCAUUUGAGUUUGUGUCCUGAGAAGUCCCAGACUCGGCUGAAGAUCUGAUUAUGUCUCUGUGCAUAUUGUACAUGUAAAUAUCUAUAAUGUAAAUGUAAUUUAAGAAUCAAAUUUUUCGAAUGGCAAUCAACUGUUUAUUAUUUAUCUAUUUAUUAUCCUGUUGAGUUGAUGAAAUAGAUGAUUUCUUUUUAAAUAUAUAAUUUAUAUAACUUAUCCUGAUUUUCUGAAAAUAUGCAAUAGCCUAUGAUUUUCCUGAACUCUGUGUUGUUGGGAGAACUCUGGCCAGAAAACGUCCUGCUUAUUUAUUGCCAGAUAUGGUUUAUUUCUAAGCGUUGUCAAUAAAUGCUAUUUACACCUUU